GACUGCGCGCCCCGCCCGGAGUCCCCGCCGCCGUCAUGCAGUCCCCGGCGGUGCUCGUCACCUCCAGGCGACUUCAGAAUGCCCACACUGGCCUCGACCUGACUGUGCCCCAGCACCAGGAGGUACGGGGCAAGAUGAUGUCUGGACACGUGGAGUACCAGAUCCUGGUGGUGACCCGUCUGGCUGCGUUCAAGUCGGCCAAGCACAGGCCCGAGGAUGUCGUCCAGUUCUUGGUCUCCAAAAAGUACAGCGAGAUUGAGGAGUUUUACCAGAAACUGAGCAGUCGUUAUGCAGCAGCCAGCCUCCCCCCACUACCCAGGAAGGUCCUGUUUGUUGGGGAGUCUGACAUCCGGGAGAGGAGAGCCGUGUUCAAUGAGAUCCUGCGCUGUGUCUCCAAGGAUGCCGAGUUGGCAGGCAGCCCAGAGCUGCUAGAGUUCUUAGGUACCAGAUCCCCAGGGGCUGCAGGGCUCACCAGCAGAGAUUCCUCUGUCCUGGAUGGCACAGACAGUCAGACAGGGAAUGAUGAAGAGGCUUUCGACUUUUUUGAGGAGCAAGACCAAGUGGCAGAAGAGGGUCCGCCCGUCCAGAGCCUGAAGGGCGAGGAUGCUGAGGAAUCCUUGGAGGAGGAGGAGGCGCUGGACCCUCUGGGCAUUAUGCGCUCCAAGAAGCCCAAGAAACAUCCCAAAGUGGCCGUGAAAGCCAAGCCCUCGCCCCGGCUCACCAUCUUUGACGAGGAGGUGGACCCUGAUGAGGGGCUCUUUGGCCCGGGCAGGAAGCUGUCUCCACAGGACCCCUCGGAGGACGUGUCAUCCGUGGACCCCCUGAAGCUAUUUGAUGAUCCUGACCUCGGCGGGGCCAUCCCCCUGGGUGACUCCCUCCUGCUGCCAGCCGCCUGUGAGAGUGGAGGGCCCACACCCAGCCUCAGCCACAGGGACGCCUCCAAGGAACUGUUCAGGACACUGGCUCAUAAGGGAUUUCAAUGUGCACAGAGCAACUGCCUCCUCACCUCCCCACGGAUUCCACUACAACCAUCUAGGAGGACCACAGCAGCUUCGUCUAGCCUUCCCCUUCCCCCAGGAUCCUGGGCUGGGGUGGAGGAGGAGGCGCCACUGCAGAUCCAGUAUGGUGAGAGAACUGUCCUACACUUCCAAAUUAUCUCAUCUCCCCUCUGCACCCCCAUCCCUGGCUGCUGGUGUCAAGAGGAAAGCAACCCGCUCAACUAAAUCACAUGGAUACAGACGCAGUGAACAAUGUCCAAGUGGGUCCUUGAAAAGUAGCCUCUAUCUGGGGAUGCUAAGUCUGGAGGGAGAGGGAGGUGCUCUUUCGAGGGGCAGCCAGCAGCCUGGUGCCCUCUGCUUUGCAGAACUUGGGAUAAGGCAGAAACCCUGCCGGGUCAGACCAGGGCUCCUCAAGAGGCCUGGGGCUCACUUGCCCUCCUCAAGGCUUUGAGGACCCCUUGGGGAACUGCCUCUCCUCUUGUUGCCCUAAACCCACACCAUCUUGGCACCUGGCCCCUGCAGGGUUCUGCAUUCCUGAACCAGGAGAGAGCCAUGUUCAGGAAUGCAGGCUGACUUCUCAGCAGCUCUGCAUCCAUCACAAAUAGCUGAUGCUCUCCGAAGGCCUCUAGAAACCUGCAGAGCACCCUCCUUGCCUUUCUCUGUGUCUUUCCAGCUUUCUCAGAGGGACCCAAAGACUUCCAGAGGGGAGCUUUCCACUCCUGAUAGUAGAUAAAGGAUGGCUUCUCUAUCCCAUCCAAAUGCUAUAGAAAUGUACACGUGUGGAAAUCCCUAUCAACAUGACAAAGAGUUCAUCAGGGUCAGAGAUUUGUGUUGGAAAAUGGGAAGAGGAUUAUACUGAACUAAUGACUAAACCAGAUCAAAGAAGUCACAACCUAAAAGUGGCCCAACAGAGAUCAGCAGCAGAGUCUCCAUAGAGGGUCAAGCCAGGAGGCCCAGCCGUCAUCAUUCAGAGUCCUAGAAAAUGGAGAAAAUAACCGCUGUUGGAAAAUACAGGUCUUUGUCUGGAAGGCAGGACAUCCUAAAAUACCCUUAUGAAAUUUCGGAAGGCCAAUGAUAAGAUCUUAGCUUCCAGAAAAUAAAAAAAGAGGUCACUUGCAAGAAAAGGGAAUCGCAUUAGCAUCAGAAUUUGCAUUUGCAUCAGAAUUUACAACAGCAUAGAUGCUAGAGGUCAAUGGGAUCAGAGAGAAAAUGAUUUUGAACCUUCAAUUCUACAACUAGGCAAACUAUCAAUUAAAUACCCUUUCAGACAAAGAUUGUUUGAGGACAUAUUACAUGCAAAAUUAGAAAGGAAUCUGAAAGACAGGAAGGCAUGGGGUAGAACGAACAGUGGAAUUAGCGCAGUGUGGUGCCCUGAAAGGAAAUCCCAGCUGCGGGCUGCACAGGAACCAGAAAGCCAGUUCAGAACCUUCCCCACUGAUUACAAAUCUGGGUGAUUUUAAGGACAUGGAAAAGAAGAGUGUGUUUCUUCUUUGGAUGAGAAAUGAAAGGCAGAACAAGAAGGAGCCAGGAAAAAGAACAAACUGAACACGGCAGUCAUGGCCCAAAUAUGUACAAUUUAAACUAAAAUGCAGCAACUGAUGGGUUUGAGAAGCUGAUGGCGUGUGCAGUAAGAGAAUCCCUCUGACCCCAAGUCUUGUGUCUUCUUCAAGCAGCCUAGGUUUAGUGACUUGAGAAUACAGUUGCUUCUCUGAGGGGCCAACCUGGUACUGUUUUUGUAAUCAUAGUACUAUAAGAGCUAUGUUGAAAUCGACCUAUAGACAAAGCCCAGAAGUCAUAGCUUAGAAAUGCGGUAACCUUGAUCAUAUAAAAGAAGUUAAUAAAGUAAAAGAAUUUGAUAAUAUA